ACAGGAAAGCGCCCCGCGCUCACGCAGCCCCUCACACCCGCAGCCCCGCUUACACGCGCCCCAGCUCACACAUGCACCCCAGUCACACAGCCUACCUCACACACGCACCCCAGUCACACACACAACCCAGCUCACACACGUACCCGUCACACAUGAGGCCCCAGCUCACACACGAAGCCCAGCUCACACACGCAGCCCCAGCUCUCACACACACACCCCAGUCAAACACGAGGCCCCAGCUCACACACGAAGCCCAGCUCACACACACUGCCCCAGUUACACAGCCCAGCUCAUGCAAGCAGCCCGUCACACACACAGCCCAGCUCACACACACAGCCCAGCUCACACAAGCAGCCCGUCACACACACAGCCCAGCUCACACACACAGCCCCAGUUAUACACACACAGCCCAGCUCACACACGCAGCCCGUCACACACACAGCUCAGCUCAAUACACAGCCCAGCUCACACACACAGCCCCAGUUACACACACAGCCCAGCUUACACACACAGCCCAGCUCACACACACAGCCCAUCACACACACAGCCUAUCACACACACAGCUCAGCUCAAUACACAGCCCAGCUGACACACGCAGCCCAGCUCACACAUACACUCCAGCUCACACACGCAGCCCGUCACACAGCCCCAGCCACACACACAGCCCAGCUCACACACGCAGCCCAGCUCACACAUGCAGCCCCCUCACACAUGCAGCCCCAGUCACACACACAGCCCAGCUCACACCGCAGCCCCAGCUCACACACGCGGCCCCUCACACACAUUCAGCCGCCCUUCCCGCAGCUGCCAGGCUCGGAACGGGCGGUGUCUGUGGGGGCCGCCCCGUUUCCCGGCCGCGCAAACAAGCGGCUCCUUCUCUCUGCCCCGCCAAAGAAAGGCCGCUUGUCAGGGGCGGGCGGGCAGGCGGCAGCGGCAGGCGCCCAACACUGCGGCCUUGUCCCACGCGGGCAGCCUGGGCAGGAGCAGGCCGAGGGGUGCAAGGGGCCGCUACCUUGCGGAAACCUCCCUCCCUCGGCCCUGCGGACCGCGGAGAGGCACCUUUCCACCACCGGACACCCAAGCAACAGCCCUCGCUCCAUCCGCGCUCUCCCGGCUCCCCCUCUCCUCGGGCCGCCCAUCUCUCCUCUCUUCCGCCUUUGGGGUCCCGGUGGGCCCCAGCCUCCCUCUCCUUCGCCCCAUCUCCCCGCCCGUCAGCCUCCCCUCCGCUGCCCUCGCGCAUCCCCAGUGUUCCCGUCUGUCGUCGCCUCCACUUGAGGACCCGCCUGUCCUUUCUUCCCCCGACCCCUCCACCUCUGUGUUCUUCAGUCUCCCCGCAUCCUCUGCCCUCGGUCUUCCCCUCCCCAGCUUGCAUUUUUUCCCAUCUCUUAGUCUGCCUUUCAUUUUCCCCUUCACAUCCCGGUGGCUCCCCUUCCCCGCCCCGUCCCUCUGCACACCCCCAUUCAUCUCUGUCAGGUUUUUCUCAUCCUUAAGUUCUCUCGUCCCCCUCCCCACUCGGGCGUCCCCCGCUGGGCUCCCCGCCUCAGUUUCCUUCCCUUCCUGACUCCUUCCUCUGACGGCGGCCCUUUCUCGAGGGCGGAUGUGCGCCUGGAGGGCGAAGGCGGCGGCCGAGAGGACCCCAGCUCGGCCUGGCGGGCCUCUGGCCACAGCCAUGCACCGCUUGGGCCGAGGCCGAGGCCGACCCCCAGGGACACAGGAGCUCUGGAGCCUUAGGACCAUGGACGCUCUCAAUAGGAACCAAAUAGGCCCUGGAUGCCAGACCCAGACCAUGGUGCAGAAAGGACCCUUGGACCUGAUCGAGACAGGCAAAGGGCUGAAAGUGCAAACGGACAAACCCCACCUGGUGAGCCUGGGCAGUGGGCGACUCAGCACAGCCAUCACCCUCCUGCCGCUGGAGGAAGGGAGGACGGUGAUUGGCUCUGCAGCCAGAGACAUCUCACUACAGGGCCCAGGCCUGGCUCCAGAGCACUGCUACAUCGAGAACCUGCGGGGCACCCUCACCCUCUACCCCUGUGGCAAUGCCUGCACUAUUGAUGGGCUCCCUGUCCGGCAGCCUACCCGGCUCACUCAGGGCUGCAUGUUGUGCCUGGGUCAGUCCACCUUCCUUCGCUUUAACCACCCGGCUGAAGCCAAGUGGAUGAAAAGCAUGAUUCCAGCAGGGGGCCGAGCCCCUGGGCCCCCCUACAGCCCUGUUCCUGCAGAAUCAGAAAGUCUGGUAAAUGGGAACCACACCCCACAGACUGCAACACGGGGACCCUCUGCCUGUGCCAGCCACAGUUCCCUGGUGAGCUCUAUUGAGAAGGACCUGCAAGAGAUCAUGGACUCACUGGUGCUAGAGGAGCCUGGAGCUGCUGGCAAGAAGCCUGCCGCAACCUCUCCACUGUCACCGAUGGCUAAUGGUGGGCGCUACCUGCUGUCUCCCCCAACCAGCCCCGGCGCCAUGUCUGUGGGCUCCAGCUAUGAGAACACCUCUCCAGCCUUCUCUCCACUCUCUUCACCAGCCAGCAGUGGAAGCUGUGCCAGUCACUCACCCAGUGGGCAAGAGCCAGGACCUUCUGUGCCCCCGCUGGUACCUGCCCGUUCCUCCAGCUACCAUCUGGCCCUACAGCCCCCACAGUCCCGCCCAAGUGGUGCUCGCUCCGAGAGUCCUCGGCUGAGCAGGAAAGGGGGCCAUGAGAGGCCUCCCAGCCCUGGCCUCCGGGGUCUGCUGACAGACAGCCCUGCAGCUACUGUCUUGGCGGAGGCCCGGAGAGCCACUGAGAGCCCCCGGCUGGGUGGGCAGCUGCCUGUGGUGGCCAUCAGCCUGAGUGAAUACCCAGCUUCUGGUGCUCUCAGUCAACCCACCAGCAUUCCUGGCAGCCCCAAGUUUCAGCCUCCAGUCCCUGCUCCCCGAAACAAGAUUGGCACACUCCAGGACCGCCCUCCCAGCCCUUUCCGUGAGCCUCCAGGCAGUGAGCGGGUGCUAACAACCAGCCCCUCACGCCAACUGGUGGGCCGAACAUUUUCAGAUGGGUUAGCCACCCGUACCCUGCAGCCUCCUGAGAGUCCCCGCCUGGGCCGGCGGGGCCUGGACAGUAUGCGAGAACUACCCCCCUUAAGUCCAUCUCUGUCCCGGCGAGCUCUCUCCCCGCUGCCCACCCGGACCACCCCAGAUCCCAAGCUAAACAGGGAAGUGGCAGAGAGUCCUCGGCCCCGGCGCUGGGCAGCCCAUGGGGCUUCACCAGAGGACUUCUCCCUGACGCUGGGGGCACGGGGCCGUAGGACACGGAGCCCCUCACCCACACUGGGUGAGUCUCUGGCACCCCACAAGGGCAGCUUCAGUGGCAGGCUGAGCCCAGCCUACAGUCUGGGCUCUCUUACUGGGGCUUCACCCUGCCAGAGUCCCUGUGUCCAGAGGAAGCUCUCCAGCGGGGACUUGCGGGUGCCUGUCACAAGGGAGCGGAAAAAUAGCAUCACAGAGAUCAGUGACAAUGAGGACGACCUCCUGGAGUACCACCGGCGACAGCGCCAAGAGCGGCUCCGGGAGCAGGAGAUGGAGAGGCUGGAACGCCAGCGCCUGGAGACCAUCCUGAACCUGUGUGCCGAAUACAGCCGGGCUGAUGGGGGACCUGAGGCUGGGGAGCUUCCCAGCAUUGGGGAGGCCACCGCAGCAUUGGCACUGGCAGGCCGGAGGCCCUCACGAGGCCUUGCAGGGGCCUCUGGGCGGAGCAGCGAGGAGCCUGGCGUUGCCACCCAACGCCUAUGGGAGAGUAUGGAGCGCUCAGAUGAGGAAAAUCUCAAGGAGGAGUGCAGCAGCACUGAGAGCACCCAGCAGGAGCACGAAGAUGCACCUAGCACCAAGCUCCAGGGAGAGGUGCUAGCCCUGGAAGAAGAGCGGGCUCAGGUGCUGGGGCACGUGGAGCAGCUCAAGGUCCGUGUGAAGGAGCUAGAGCAGCAGCUGCAGGAGUCAGCCCGAGAGGCCGAAAUGGAGCGGGCACUGCUGCAGGGAGAGAGGGAGGCAGAGCGGGCACUGCUGCAGAAGGAGCAGAAGGCAGUGGAUCAGCUGCAGGAGAAGCUGGUGGCCUUGGAGACAGGCAUCCAGAAGGAGAGGGACAAGGAGGCAGAGGCCCUGGAGACUGAGACAAAGCUCUUUGAGGACUUGGAGUUCCAGCAGUUGGAGCGGGAGAGCCGCGUGGAGGAGGAGCGCGAGCUGGCCGGCCAGGGGCUGCUCCGGAGCAAGGCUGAGCUGCUCCGCAGCAUCGCCAAGAGGAAGGAGCGCCUGGCCAUCCUGGACAGUCAGGCUGGGCAGAUCCGGGCUCAGGCCGUGCAGGAAUCAGAACGCCUGGCCCGGGACAAGAAUGCCUCCUUACAGCUGCUGCAAAAGGAGAAGGAGAAGCUGACUGUGCUGGAAAGGAGAUACCACUCACUCACAGGGGGCAGGCCUUUCCCGAAGACCACAUCGACCCUCAAAGAGGUUUACCGCUCCAAGAUGGAUGGCGAGGCCACCAGCCCCCUUCCCCGGACCCGCAGCGGCCCCCUCCCCUCCUCCUCUGGCUCUUCCUCCUCCUCCUCCCAGCUCAGCGUGGCUACCCUGGGGCGUAGCCCCUCCCCAAAGAGCGCUCUACUCACCCAGAAUGGCACGGGCAGCCUUCCUCGCAACCUGGCAGCCACACUGCAGGACAUCGAGACCAAGCGCCAACUAGCUCUGCAGCAGAAGGGACAACAAGUGAUUGAAGAGCAGCGGCGGCGACUGGCUGAGCUGAAGCAGAAAGCGGCAGCUGAGGCACAGUGCCAGUGGGAUGCCCUUCACGGGGCAGCACCCUUCCCAGCGGGCCCCUCGGGCUUCCCCCCUCUCAUGCACCACUCUAUCCUACACCACCUGCCUGCGGGGCGGGAGCGUGGGGAGGAGGGUGAGCACGCCUAUGAUACGCUGAGUCUGGAGAGCUCUGACAGCAUGGAGACCAGCAUCUCCACCGGGGGCAACUCGGCCUGCUCCCCUGACAACAUGUCCAGCGCGAGUGGUCUGGACAUGGGGAAGAUCGAGGAGAUGGAGAAGAUGCUGAAAGAGGCUCAUGCAGAGAAGAACCGGCUCAUGGAGUCGAGGGAGCGGGAGAUGGAGCUGCGGCGGCAGGCCCUGGAGGAGGAGCGGCGGAGGCGUGAGCAGGUAGAACGGAGGCUGCAGAGUGAGAGUGCCCGGAGGCAGCAGCUGGUCGAGAAGGAGGUCAAGAUGCGGGAGAAACAAUUUUCCCAGGCACGACCCCUGACCCGCUACCUGCCAAUCCGGAAGGAGGACUUUGACCUGAAGACACAUAUUGAGUCAUCGGGCCAUGGUGUUGAUACCUGCCUGCACGUGGUGCUCAGCAGCAAGGUCUGCCGUGGCUACUUGGUCAAGAUGGGCGGCAAGAUUAAAUCAUGGAAGAAGCGCUGGUUUGUCUUCGACCGGCUCAAGCGCACCCUUUCCUAUUAUGUGGACAAGCAUGAGACGAAGCUGAAGGGAGUCAUCUAUUUCCAGGCCAUUGAGGAAGUGUACUACGACCACCUGCGCAGUGCAGCCAAGAGCCCGAACCCAGCCCUCACCUUCUGCGUAAAGACCCAUGACCGGCUGUACUACAUGGUGGCCCCAUCUGCAGAGGCCAUGCGUAUCUGGAUGGAUGUCAUUGUCACAGGGGCUGAGGGCUACACUCAGUUCAUGAACUAACUGCCGUGGGCCUCCUGGCAGAGCACAACUGGGGCUUUUGUAUAAGAAGACUUUAAUAUUCUGUAAGGAGCUUGGUCCUGUGAGUUUCUGGGCUCUGGCCUCCUGAAGAACCAGCCAGAAGAAGAAAAGUAGAGGUGGCUUUGCUGCCUCCUGGGAGCCCAGAACUUGCAGUAACCCUUUAGGGUCCUGCCCCAGGCCCAGCCAGGGCUGAGGAGCUGUCACAGAGAGGGCCUCAGCUCUGACCUGACACCUGCUCUCCCCAGCCUGUUUUCUCUUUUCUAAAAGACAAAUUAUGGUACCAUAAGCUGCCAAAGAUCCCCUCCUGCCUCAGACCCCUUUGCCAGGGGCUUUGGGGGCUGAGCAGAGCCACAUCCAGAGUGGGGUAAUAGCUCAGGCGGCCCGCUUCCCAUUUCUCAAACCCCGCUCUGCCCCAUUGUUCUCCUUUCCCUUAUACUUUUUAUUACCUUGCUCAAGGGCCAGAGAUCUCAAGUGUCAACCUUGAGGUCCCAGCUCCAUCCCCUAGUUGCAGACUCAUCACCAUGGUUACCAUAGUGACUGCUUCAUUGCCAUGGUUACAUACUAAUUGCUGCAGCUCUGUGGCCCAGCCCACUGCUUCAGCUGUGGGCCAUCUGAGGGUACGUGCCAUCAUCUCUCCAGCCCAGGCCCCUGGGCAUCUCAUGCUGGGGGGAAGGGACUGAAUACCUUUUUCCUUCCCCCUGCCUGUGUCUUCAGCCCUGAUGCACAGGCUGCCAGCCCCCCAGUCCAGCCCUCUCCCUUCCACUGGUGCCUUGCUUAGAGCCAGAAGGGAUGAAGCCGGGGGAUCUAUGGAACAGAGGAGGAGCGAUGCAGUUGGGAGAGGAAGCUAGAAGGGUUAUGGUUGGAGUUCUGUACAGUGUUGAGUUUCCGACAGGGAAAGAGGAUUCCUCCAAUGCUCCUAGAGAGAAAGCCUGAGCAGGAGAUGAUGCAGCAGAGGGGAAGGGCCCUGUGGUGCCGCCGCCCUUCCUUCAGCCUCCGAAGGGUGAUGGAAAUGGAGAGUGGAGGACCAGGCCUCCAGCUGUCUGGCCUCGCCCUUCACGCCUUAACACUAAGCCCACCUCCCCUGCUCUCCUUCCCAGCAUUGAGCCCUUGGUUGCCUGGGCCCAGGCUGGGGGUUUUCAGUAUUUGUAAGCAUUUCAGCAGAACAAUAAAGCCUUUGGACUACGGAA